ACUCCGCUCACUUCCCCGGCCCCGCGCGGCCCCCGCCGCCCGCUGCCCGCUGCCCGCUGCCCUCGCCCCGCGCGCCGGGCAUGUGAGCGCGGGCGGGCGCCGUCACCAUGGCCUCGCCGCGCGCCUCGCGGUGGCCGCCGCCGCUCCUGCUGCUGUUGCUGCCGCUGCUGCUGCUGCCGCCGGCGGCCCCCGGGACGCGGGACCCGCCGCCUUCCCCGGCUCGCCGCGCGCUGAGCCUGGCGCCCCUCGCGGGAGCGGGGCUGGAGCUGCAGCUGGAGCGCCGCCCGGAGCGCGAGCCGCCGCCCACGCCGCCCCGGGAGCGCCGCGGGCCCGCGACCCCCGGCCCCAGCUACAGGGCCCCUGAGCCAGGCGCCGCGACACAGCGGGGACCCUCCGGCCGGGCCCCCAGAGGCGGGAGCGCGGAUGCUGCCUGGAAACAUUGGCCAGAAAGUAACACUGAGGCCCAUGUAGAAAACAUCACCUUCUAUCAGAAUCAAGAGGACUUUUCAACAGUGUCCUCCAAAGAGGGCGUGAUGGUUCAGACCUCUGGGAAGAGCCAUGCUGCUUCGGAUGCUCCAGAAAACCUCACUCUACUCGCUGAAACAGCAGAUGCUAGAGGAAGGAGCGGCUCUUCAAGUAGAACAAACUUCACCAUUUUGCCUGUUGGGUACUCACUGGAGAUAGCAACAGCUCUGACUUCCCAGAGUGGCAACUUAGCCUCAGAAAGUCUUCACCUGCCAUCCAGCAGUUCAGAGUUCGAUGAAAGAAUUGCCGCUUUUCAAACAAAGAGUGGAACAGCCUCGGAGAUGGGAACAGAGAGGGCGAUGGGGCUGUCAGAAGAAUGGACUGUGCACAGCCAAGAGGCCACCACUUCGGCUUGGAGCCCGUCCUUUCUUCCUGCUUUGGAGAUGGGAGAGCUGACCACGCCUUCUAGGAAGAGAAAUUCCUCAGGACCAGAUCUCUCCUGGCUGCAUUUCUACAGGACAGCAGCUUCCUCUCCUCUCUUAGACCUUUCCUCAUCUUCUGAAAGUACAGAGAAGCUUAACAACUCCACUGGCCUCCAGAGCUCCUCAGUCAGUCAAACAAAGACAAUGCAUGUUGCCACCGUGUUCACUGAUGGUGGCCCGAGAACGCUGCGAUCUUUGACGGUCAGUCUGGGACCUGUGAGCAAGACAGAAGGCUUCCCCAAGGACUCCAGAAUUGCCACGACUUCAUCCUCAGUCCUUCUUUCACCCUCUGCAGUGGAAUCGAGAAGAAACAGUAGAGUAACUGGGAAUCCAGGGGAUGAGGAAUUCAUUGAACCAUCCACAGAAAAUGAAUUUGGACUUACGUCUUUGCGUUGGCAAAAUGAUUCCCCAACCUUUGGAGAACAUCAGCUUGCCAGCAGCUCUGAGGUGCAAAAUGGAAGUCCCAUGUCUCAGACUGAGACUGUGUCUAGGUCAGUCGCACCCAUGAGAGGUGGAGAGAUCACUGCACACUGGCUCUUGACCAACAGCACAACAUCUGCAGAUGUGACAGGAAGCUCUGCUUCAUAUCCUGAAGGUGUGAAUGCUUCAGUGUUGACCCAGUUCUCAGACUCUACUGUACAGUCUGGAGGAAGUCACACAGCAUUGGGAGAUAGGAGUUAUUCAGAGUCUUCAUCUACAUCUUCCUCGGAAAGCUUGAAUUCAUCAGCACCACGUGGAGAACGUUCGAUCGCUGGGAUUAGCUACGGUCAAGUGCGUGGCACAGCUAUUGAACAAAGGACUUCCAGCGACCACACAGACCACACCUACCUGUCAUCUACUUUCACCAAAGGAGAACGGGCGUUACUGUCCAUUACAGAUAACAGUUCAUCCUCAGACAUUGUGGAGAGCUCAACUUCUUAUAUUAAAAUCUCAAACUCUUCACAUUCAGAGUAUUCCUCCUUUUUUCAUGCUCAGACUGAGAGAAGUAACAUCUCAUCCUAUGACGGGGAAUAUGCUCAGCCUUCUACUGAGUCGCCAGUUCUGCAUACAUCCAACCUUCCGUCCUACACACCCACCAUUAAUAUGCCGAACACUUCGGUUGUUCUGGACACUGAUGCUGAGUUUGUUAGUGACUCCUCCUCCUCCUCUUCCUCCUCCUCCUCUUCUUCUUCUUCAGGGCCUCCUUUGCCUCUGCCCUCUGUGUCACAAUCCCACCAUUUAUUUUCAUCAAUUUUACCAUCAACCAGGGCCUCUGUGCAUCUACUAAAGUCUACCUCUGAUGCAUCCACACCAUGGUCUUCCUCACCAUCACCUUUACCAGUAUCCUUAACGACAUCUACAUCUGCCCCACUUUCUGUCUCACAAACAACCUUGCCACAGUCAUCUUCUACCCCUGUCCUGCCCAGGGCAAGGGAGACUCCUGUGACUUCAUUUCAGACAUCAACAAUGACAUCAUUCAUGACAAUGCUCCAUAGUAGUCAAACUGCAGACCUUAAGAGCCAGAGCACCCCACACCAAGAGAAAGUCAUUACAGAAUCAAAGUCACCAAGCCUGGUGUCUCUGCCCACAGAGUCCACCAAAGCUGUAACAACAAACUCUCCUUUGCCUCCAUCCUUAACAGAGUCCUCCACAGAGCAAACCCUUCCAGCCACAAGCACCAACUUAGCACAAAUGUCUCCAACUUUCACAACUACCAUUCUGAAGACCUCUCAGCCUCUUAUGACCACUCCUGGCACCCUGUCAAGCACAGCAUCUCUGGUCACUGGCCCUAUAGCCGUACAGACUACAGCUGGAAAACAGCUCUCGCUGACCCAUCCUGAAAUACUAGUUCCUCAAAUCUCAACAGAAGGUGGCAUCAGCACAGAAAGGAACCGAGUGAUUGUGGAUGCUACCACUGGAUUGAUCCCUUUGACCAGUGUACCCACAUCAGCAAAAGAAAUGACCACAAAGCUUGGCGUUACAGCAGAGUACAGCCCAGCUUCACGUUCCCUCGGAACAUCUCCUUCUCCCCAAACCACAGUUGUUUCCACGGCUGAAGACUUGGCUCCCAAAUCUGCCACCUUUGCUGUUCAGAGCAGCACACAGUCACCAACAACAGUGUCCUCUUCAGCCUCAGUCAACAGCUGUGCUGUGAACCCUUGUCUUCACAAUGGCGAAUGCGUCGCAGACAACACCAGCCGUGGCUACCACUGCAGGUGCCCGCCUUCCUGGCAAGGGGAUGAUUGCAGUGUGGAUGUGAAUGAGUGCCUGUCGAACCCCUGCCCAUCCACAGCCAUGUGCAACAAUACUCAGGGAUCCUUUAUCUGCAAAUGCCCGGUUGGGUACCAGUUGGAAAAAGGGAUAUGCAAUUUGGUUAGAACCUUCGUGACAGAGUUUAAAUUAAAGAGAACUUUUCUUAAUACAACUGUGGAAAAACAUUCAGACCUACAAGAAGUUGAAAAUGAGAUCACCAAAACGUUAAAUAUGUGUUUUUCAGCGUUACCUAGUUACAUCCGAUCUACAGUUCACGCCUCUAGGGAGUCCAACGCGGUGGUGAUCUCACUGCAAACAACCUUUUCCCUGGCCUCCAAUGUGACGCUAUUUGACCUGGCUGAUAGGAUGCAGAAAUGUGUCAACUCCUGCAAGUCCUCUGCUGAGGUCUGCCAGCUCUUGGGAUCUCAGAGGCGGAUCUUUAGAGCGGGCAGCUUGUGCAAGCGGAAGAGUCCCGAAUGUGACAAAGACACCUCCAUCUGCACUGACCUGGACGGCGUUGCCCUGUGCCAGUGCAAGUCGGGAUACUUUCAGUUCAACAAGAUGGACCACUCCUGCCGAGCAUGUGAAGAUGGAUAUAGGCUUGAAAAUGAAACCUGCAUGAGUUGCCCAUUUGGCCUUGGUGGUCUCAACUGUGGAAACCCCUAUCAGCUUAUCACUGUGGUGAUCGCAGCCGCGGGAGGUGGGCUCCUGCUCAUCCUAGGCAUCGCACUGAUUGUUACCUGUUGCAGAAAGAAUAAAAAUGACAUAAGCAAACUCAUCUUCAAAAGUGGAGAUUUCCAAAUGUCCCCGUAUGCUGAAUACCCCAAAAAUCCUCGCUCACAAGAAUGGGGCCGAGAAGCUAUUGAAAUGCAUGAGAAUGGAAGUACCAAAAACCUCCUCCAGAUGACGGAUGUGUACUACUCGCCUACAAGUGUAAGGAAUCCAGAACUUGAACGAAACGGACUCUACCCGGCCUACACUGGACUGCCAGGAUCACGGCAUUCUUGCAUUUUCCCCGGACAGUAUAACCCGUCUUUCAUCAGUGAUGAAAGCAGAAGAAGAGACUACUUUUAAGUCCAGGAGAGAGAGGGACUCAUUGCUCUGAGCCAGUCACCUGGGACCUCUGCUCAGAGGACCGCACCAGGAGGCUGCGCCCAGGAUUUGUCGGGAGCCACGCUGAGUGGCAAGCAGGAAGAGGGACAGGCAUGCGGGGCGUGACCACAGUGGAGGAGACAGGUGGAUGUGGAACCACAGGCUGCUCAUUCAGCACCUUUGUUGUUACUGUGAACGUGAAUGUGGGCCAGUAUCAAGAGAGUCUCUCUGAGUGACUGCACCAUGGCACUGGCACCAGGGCGACUAUUAGCCAGGGCAGACCACUAGACUUCAGUGCAGGGACCUGGUUUUCCCUUCGUUUGCACUUUAGUAAAUUGGGUGGGAGGUUUCCUUUUGGAUCUGUUUUGAGACUGUUCCAGAAAGAAGGCUUCCUUUCCCGAGACACUUCCAUAGGCAGCAAUUUGGUGAUUCAUUUGCAGCAAAAUACUGGCUUGUUAAUUAUUUUCCUGCCCAGCGCCUGCGUGCUAAACAACAGAUGAGGAUGAGCGUACCACUGAAGUCUGAAGAUGUCGCCAUUGAACGGACAGUGUUUUCAUAUGUUUCUAGGUUGUCUUAUGCUACAGUUUCCAAGCCAGCCCCCACAGUGAGGAAAUGUGUGAGGCACCGCACACAACUGCAAUGUGUUUUUUAAGUCAAGGUGACACAUGUAUUUAAGAUUUUUUUUUUAAAUCUCUUUGCAGUUAAAUCUCACUUUUUCAAACAAGCCUGGAUCAGGGCAAAACAACUUAUAUUUGGUUUUAGCUGGAGGCUCAGCAGGCAGAUUGCAGGCAGGGGGGCACUUUUCAUCCAUGAGGGCCCAGCCUGGGGCCUGGGACUCGAUCACCAUUGUGGAGGCCAGAGGCAGCUGCGUAUGGAGGAGAAAUGUCAAACUGAACGCAGGUUUCACCACUCUAGGAAAGCAGCUUGUUGAGCCCCUGCAGCUGGAUGUGGUUAGAGGGAUGGGCUGAAUAGGCAGGUUAGAUUUCCUGCAUCAACAGUGCUUUGGGAAGCUGUGUGGAUUCCUGAGGAAGAACAGGGAGCCGAGAUGGAGCCACACAUGAGUUUGCUCACCGGCUACUGCAGCACUUUGUACCCAGAAUCUCAUGUCCACAAACCCCAUGUAAACUUUCAACCACUCAAAGCUGUUUAUUCGGCUGAAGAAAUAACUUUUUUUUCUCACCCAGUCAUUUGUACCUCUUCAUAUGGCUAUGUCGCACCCUCCAGAAACGUGGUUAUACUUCCAGUCAGUGUGGGAGAACUGAAGACUUCCGGUUGGUCGAGGAACUGAGGGUUGACCUUCGGGAAGGAAGUUCCACUCAUCUUAUUUAUUAUGCCUGUGAUGUGGGUCCUGCCAGGGAGACAUCCAGUACUCGGUGUCUUUAAUUGCCACCUGGGGAACUGUGUUUAUUGGCCUUCUUUGGGGCAUCCUGGUUUUGGAUGAAGUGAGGGGAAUACAGAGGUAAAAGAAUUGUCUCCACCCUGAAGCGGGGAGUCCCGCUUCACAUUUCUGGAAAUGGUGCAGCCACUGGGGACAGUUCUGCCCCGGGCAUGGUUGUUUCUUCAAGGUCCUCUAAAUAUAAUCCCUAUUCUUACAUAAUCCUUGGCCCUGAUGGUUUUAAGCAAGAACUCCUGUGUCCCAUGGUCUCCACCACUCACCAUCACCCUGCUGUAGCAAGAGUCCUAGUCAGGGGAGGUGCAUUUUAGUAGUUACAUUGCACUUAUCCAUGAGAUAAAUAAAAGGAGAACUGUUUUUAUCAGUGGAGGCUAACCUAAAAUUUCAAAGUGUCGCCUUUUUGAAAUCUUGGGCCUCUCUCUCUGUAGAACCAAUGGCCCUUUGUGGCUCACGGCCUCGCACCUAACUGGAGAGUUCUGAGCUCCUGCAGCUCACCUGAGCCCACAGACUAGGCUUCUUGGCUCCUUCCGCAGCAUGCCUGCUCACCCCCAGAACCCGCAGCUGUGGGAAGAGCCAUGUAGGGAGGCUAUUCCCAGGCAUACACUUCCACUGCCUUCAGCUGACGUCACAGCUGACAAAUCAUCUCCUCUAUCGGAGCCAGAAGACUUCAGCUCCACAAAAUGAAGUGUUCUGUCCUGAAAACAUUCUUGGGAAGAAUCCCAACAUCGAGAAAACGGUGUCCUGUGAGUUCCAACAAUGCUUCUUGUUCAUGGGUUUCUUCCGUAUGGAGUGGAUUAAGAGUGUUUUAUUUUGUUGUUCUAACUGAGAAAAAAAGGAGGCACCCACAAGGUUGAGGUCACACAGUCUCCACAGUUUCCAGGAGGCGUUUGGGGGUGGGGAAGGCACCUCCAGAGCAUGAGGCUCUAAGGGGACAUGAGUAAAGCAUGUCUGUGACCCAGUGAGGAAGGGAGAGGCCAGCUGCACUCCUGCACGGGGUUCCUAGCUGCAGAAGGGUCCCGCCUAGGCCGAGGGGAAACACCUGAUAGCAGAAGAGGCCUGGAUGCACACCUGGCACGCCGAGGCUCUCCGCCCAGACACAGUGCUCCAUGUCAGCCCCUGCACCUGGGGUGUGUGAUUCACGUGCACAGAUGCCACAAUCCUGCACCAAUAUCCCACAGAUGGGGGAAGGUGAGAGGAAGGGGCAAGUGAUGUGUAACUGCUCAAGAGAUGCUUAAACCUCCAUAGAGAGGAGCCGGGCGCAGGGGCAUCUGUGUGUCCCGUCACACACUGCAGCAGGGAAGGGUGGCUGGCUGGCUCCCUGGCAUCAGUGGUUUGGUUUAAGCUCCAGAGGGUCUUAUUGCCAUUGUCUUUUCCUCUGCCCCUUGAGCCAGCCUAAGGCCCUGGAGUCUGUUUCUUUAGGCGGAUGAACUGACAUGCUCCUACCAUGACCAGGCUCUGGGCAAGGCUCCUCACAGUAUCCUUGAGAGGUGGGCAUGGAAGUGCCCAUUUCUCAGGUACAGAAACCUUCAGAGAGGAUAAAUAGCUUGCCCUGUAGAAGCAGGACUGAAACCCUUGUCUGCCUGACUCCCCCAGCUACUCUGCCCACUGUAGCCCCCUGCCUUACUGUCCUGGCACACCCCUCACCAUCCUGUAUACCUUAAAUAUCAAAGAGGGCAAGAGAGAAAGGGCUUUAAAGAUAAGUUAUUUUUUUAAGGAACCUUAAUAUUAUUUUUAAGAAGUAACCAAAUUAGUGACGUGAAAUGCAAAAAAAAAAAAAAAAAAAUGCUGACUACCCUUUUGAAAAUGUGCUUUCAGAUUGUUUUUUAUAUGUAAUUCUUAGACACUUGUCAUUAAGAAAAUAGUGGCUGGCUUGUGCUCAGCAAGAAGCACACUGGCACGUGGCUUUGGUAUAGGAAGUGGAAGGCAAGGACCUGGGUUUCUGACAAGUGCAGUCAGACAUACACAUCCAUCUGAGAGCUGCUUGCCUUGUUCCCGUGGUAAGGCCAUGGCUCCCACAUACUGGAAGCAUAUUUUUGUGAACUGUUUUCAGAAUUGGGAACAUAUUCAGUGGAAUGUCUUAAACGCUGACACAUCUUCCUCCUUUGAGGGGAAGUAUAUUUUCAGAAGCAGCUAAGACAUUUAGAGCCAAAAUUGCUGAUAGGUGGUUCAGUCAAGUUGGCUGAUGGCAUCUGAGGUCAAAAACUAAGAUGUGACGAUUGAGUUCUUAAAGAGGUAACUCUUAAAGUGGGCCCAAGGGAGAAGGCAGCAUCUUUGGACUCCUAGGCUGGAUGGCUACCCAAGAAUAUGCCAUUGAAGGAUGACACCUAUUCAGAUGUGAAAGUUCCCAGAGCAGGCACCUUUGGGUCACCCACCACGUGUGGCUUUUUGGUGCCUGCAUGAAACUGUGUUGCCCCCUGGUGAGAUGCCCGGGUGUCCUGUAAGCCGAUUUAACUCUGCCUGAGGAAGAGGAGCUGUCCACUCCAGUUGCCCUUGGCUAAGUUUAGCCUAACACACAGGGUUUUGACCCAUAGUUCUAAAAUACACAAAUUUUGAGACUACAGCACUUCUUUGGAAAGAGGAAGAAUGCAAAGUUCAGUAUUUCAAUACUUUGUAUUUUACUUGAAAUUACCCUUAGUAGCAUCUUUUUUUUCCUGUCUGAAAGCUUUUGUGUGGAUGAGAAGGGACAUUUCAUUUCCUCCCUUAACAAAGUGUCAUUCUGAGGUUCUCAUGUGUGUUUUUGGAAAUAGAGAUACUGGUUUUGUAGAGUUUGCCUUUGGGUAUGUUUUCUUUUUUUCUUAAAUCUCCAAGGAAGAGAACUGACUAAAAUAGUAGGAACAUGAAAGUAUUAAAUGCCAAUUAAUUUGUUGUAGUAAAGUAUCUUCAUUAGCGUUAUACUCCAUCAUAUCUGGUGUAAACUGCUCACAGAAAACCCUAUGAAACCAAAGGGGGACCAUUCAGGUCUAAAAAGCGACAGGUCCGAGACUGGGUCUGUCACCUGGGCAUUUUCAAAGAGGACAUUUUGAAGAAUUUGCAUAUUCAGAUUUUUAAAAUGCACUUAACAUACUUCAUUACAGAUUUCUUGGGUAGGGAGGAUGGGAUAGGCCAGGGAUGGGAUGGAGUCAGUUCUGCCUGGGAAACUAAUCCGAAUCAUUUACCUUUCUGUAUUAACCUUGGCCUGUCCUAAAAAGAGAACGACUGUUUCAUCAUGAGUUGCUCUGAGUUUUGUUAAUGUUUGUGUUGGUGGAUUGACGGUUAAAUGAAGCAUUUAGCUGGAAUAUGAACUUUGGGAGUUUUCAUGUUGUCCUGGAUUUCUCUUUGUAAACCUUUAAACCUUAGCCCCUGGUUGAUUGUGUUAAACCCAUUAUGAGAAUGUUAUUUAAAGUUGUAUUAUAAUUGCAACCUCCACUAAUUAUUCAGUACUGUAGCAGCAAAGUAUUAUUUGUAAGAAUUUGGUUAUUUUUAUACUUAUAUCCACUCUAAGUCUGGCGUUCUAGUCAGUAAAAUGAUGCAAUAAAAUUAAUAUCAUUUUCA